CUGGGGGCGGGGGGGUACACAUAUGAAUCCUUCCCAUAGACAUCAGGCUAACCCCAGCGAUCACAGUCACAGACCAUACAUGGAACCAGAAAAGCAAACCGAAAUCUCAGAAUUCUUCCUCCAGGGACUCUCAGAAAAGCCAGAGCAUCAGACCCUCCUCUUCACAAUGUUCCUCUCCACAUACCUGGUCACCAUCAUUGGAAAUGCCCUCAUUAUCCUGGCCAUCAUCACGGACUCUCACCUCCACACACCCAUGUACUUCUUUCUCUUCAACCUCUCACUCGUUGACACCCUAUUAUCCUCCACCACCGUCCCCAAGAUGCUAGCGAACAUCCAGGCUCAGAGCAGAGCCAUCCCCUUUGUGGGCUGCCUCACCCAGAUGUAUGCCUUCCACCUGUUCGGGACCAUGGACAGCUUUCUCCUGGCAGUAAUGGCCAUCGACCGCUUCGUGGCCAUUGUCCACCCACAGCGUUACUUGGUUCUCAUGUGCUCCCCUGUCUGUGGGCUGCUGCUGGGAGCAUCAUGGAUGAUCACCAACCUCCAGUCUCUCAUACACACCUGCCUCAUGGCUCAACUGACCUUCUGCGCCGGCUCUGAAAUCUCCCACUUCUUCUGUGACCUCAUGCCCCUGCUGAAGCUCUCCGGCUCAGACACGCACACCAACGAGCUGGUGAUCUUUGCUUUUGGCAUUGUCGUGGGCACCAGCCCAUUCUCCUGCAUCCUUCUCUCGUACAUCCGCAUUUUCUGGACAGUCUUUAAGAUCCCUUCUACUCGGGGCAAGUGGAAAGCCUUCUCCACCUGUGGCUUACACCUCACUGUGGUGUCACUGUCCUAUGGGACCAUCUUUGCUGUGUACUUACAGCCCACAUCCCCCAGCUCCUCCCAGAAGGACAAGGCAGCCGCCCUAAUGUGUGGGGUGUUCAUCCCCAUGCUCAACCCCUUUAUCUACAGCAUACGGAACAAGGAUAUGAAGGCAGCCCUGGGGAAGCUCAUCGGCAAAGUGGCCGUCCCCUGUCCUAGGCCAGAACAGUUAUUGGAUGUUUAUCAUGUUCCAGGAUCACUGUUGGCUGCUAGGGACACAGAGAUGCAUCCCAUCCCCUACCCUGGAGGAGUUCAGAGUCUAGCUGGGAACAGAGACAUGGAAUAAAUCCUUCCAGUACAACGUGAUAAAUGUGUCAUAAAGAGAUGAACAAAGUGUAUGAGCACCCAAAGGAAAGGUGUGCAUUUUCCCCAGGAUUUAUCUUCCCCAAAAAGAUCAGAAUAGCAAGGAUCAAACUGGCCUGAAAUUAGCCCUCCUGGAGGAUCAGCCUUUUAGGAUUGCUAUGUGAAUAAGAGUAGUUGAAAACAAGAGACGUAGCUACACUCAUUUUAGUAUUGACAAAGGCCAGGUGUGGAAGCUCAAGCCUGUGAUCCCAGCAUUUUGGGAGGCCAAGGUGGAAGGAUCACUUGAGGCCAGGAGUUUGAGACCAGCCUGGGCAACAUACAGAGACCCUAUCUCCACACACACACACAAAAUCACUUUAGCAAGACAUGGUGGUAUACGCCUGUAGUCUCAGCUAAUCAGGAGGCUGAGGCAGGCAGAUCAUUUGAGCCCAGGAGUUCAAGGUUGCAGUGAGCUAUGACUGCACCACUGCACUUCAGCAGUUUGGGAAACUGAGCAAGAUCUGUCACUCAUAGGUAGAUAGAUAGAUAGAUAGAUAGAUAGAUAGAUAGAUAGAUAGAUAGACAGACAGAUAGAUAGAGAGGAUAAGAUAAGAUAGGUAGAUAGGGUGGAUAGAUAAGAUAUGUAGAUAGAUAGAUAGAUAGAUAGAUAGAUAGAUAGAUAGAUAGAUAGAUAUACAGAUAGAUACAUAGAUAGAUAGGAUAGAUAGGUAGGUAGGUAGGUAGGUCAACCGAUCGAUAGAUCUAUCUAUUGACAGACAGAUAGAUGAUUGAUUGAUAGAUAGAUCAUAUAAGUAGAUAGAUGAUAGAUAGAUAGAUAGAUAGAUAGAUAGAUGAGAUAGGUAGGUAGGUCAGUCGAUCGAUUGAUCAAUCGAUCAACAGAUAGAUGAUAGAUAGAUGGAUGGAUAGAUAGAGAUAGAGGAGGUAGGUAGAUAGAUAGAUAGAUAGAUAGGUAGAUACAGACAGCCCAUGUAUUAGCCAGUGUUUCCUAAGUGUUGUGGAAGAACUUUGAAAAUAUUUGCAAGUGAGAUUAGCUCACGUGCUGUUCGCUUAGUCAGCCAGCAAGCCUCAGCCUCCUGGGGGGUCUUGAGACCUCCACUUGUAACUAUGACUGUGGUUGGGGCUUACUUUCUCAAUUCCCAACAGGCUUCCUGUCUCCCCACAACCCCCAGUCAAGGGGACUCUGAUGCAGACGGUCCAUCAAUCGUAGUUUGGGAACACAGACCCUAGCCUAGCUCCAAAAUCUAUGUGUUUCCUGUGACAUUCAUCGCCUGACUCUGAACCCAGUAUGAUUCUACACGCAGGGUCAGCCACAGCAGAUCAGGUGGCCCGGGGCACUUAAAAAGUUAGUGUUAUGGGUUGAACUGUGGCUCCCAAAAAAAGAUACGUGGGAGGCCAGGCGCAGUGGCUCACACCUGUAAACUCUGGCACUUUGGGAGGUUGAGUAGGGAGAAUCAUUUGAAGCUAGGAGUUCAGGACCAGCCUGAACAACAUAGUGAGAUCUCAUCCCUACAAAAAAUAAAAAUGAAAAAAGAAAAAAUUACCUGGGUGUGGUGGUGUGCACCUGUCAUCUUAGUUACUCGGGAGGCUGAGACAGGAGGACCUCUUGAGCCAAGGAGGUCGAGGCUGCAUGAGCUAUGUUCCUGCCACUGCACUCCAGCCUGGGAAACAGAGCAAGGCCCUGUCUGCAAAAGUAAUAAUAAUAAAAUAAAAAAGAUAUGUUGAAGUCCUAACCCCAAGGACCUCAGAAUGUGACCAUAUUUGAAGAUAGGGUGUUUACAGAGGUCAUUAGAUUACAGUAAGGUCAUUAGGUUGGUCCCUAAUCUGAUACGACUGGCGUCCUUAUGAAAAGGGGAGAUUUGGACACAGGCACCCACACACAUGGAGACCGCCACAUGAAGAUGGAGGCAGAGAUUGGGGUGAUGCUCCUACAAGCCAAGGAAUGCCAGGGACUGCCUGCAGACCACCAGAAGCCAGGAGAGGCGUGGAACAGGCUAUCCCUCUCAGCCCUCAGAAGGAACCAAGGAAUCAAAGCUGCUGACAACUGAUCUUUUUUUUUUUUUUUUUUUUUUGAGACGGAGUCUUGCUCUGUCAUCCCGGCUGGAUGCAGUGGCAUGAUUUUGGCUCACUGCAACCUCCACCUCCCAGGUUCAAGCAAUUCUCCUGCCUCAGCCUCCCAAGUAGCUGGGAUUACAGGCACCCACCACCACGCCCAGCUAAUUUUGUGUUUUUAGUAGAGAUGGGAUUUCACUAUGUUGGCCAGACUGGUCUCAAACUCCUGGCCUCCAGUGAUCUGCCCACCUCAGCCUCCCAAAGUGCUGGGAUUACAAGCGUGGGCCACUGCACCUGGCCCAACACCUUGAUCUCGGACUCUUAACCUCCAGAACUGUAAGACAACAAAUUUCUAUUGUUUAAGUCACCUAGUUCAUGGUAAUUUUUAAAUUUUUUUUUCUUUUAGAGACAGACAGGAUCUACUGUGUCACCCAGGCUGGAGUACAGUGGUGCAAUCAUAGCUAAAGUGCAACCUCACCUCAAACUCCUGGGCUCAAGCAAUCCUCCUGCCUCAGCCUCCUGAGUAGUUGGGACUACAGGCCUAUGCCACUGCAAUCAGCUAUAUAUAUUUGUAGAGACAGGGUCUCACUAUGUUGCCCAGGCUGGUCUCAAACUCCCGGCCUCAAGAGAUCUGCCCUCCUCGGCUUCACAAAGUGCUGGGAUUGCAGGUGUAAACCACCACACUCGGCCUGAUUUGUGGUACUUUGUUGCAACAUUGCUAGAAAACAAAUGCAGUUAGUUUAAGAAAUGUCAGCAACCUACAAAACCUACAAAGUGUCCCAGUACAUCCUCUCAAGUUUACAAUUGACCAUGUGUUCUGGCCAAGGGACCCUGGGCUAGAACUGGAGAAAAGGAUGAAGGAUUUAGAUUGCAUGGAUUCACUUACUGGGUAUCAGCAUGAUGACAAUAAUGAUGAUGACAACCGAGAUUUAUUAUCUGAACAAUGCUAACUCCUUUAUAUGCACAAUCUCAAUAAGUGUUAAGCAACACCCCUACAAGGUAGGUGCAGAAGUAAUUGUGGUUUUGCCACUGAAAGUAACAGCAGGCUGCGCAUGGUGGCUCACACCUGUAUUCCCAGCACUUUGGGAGGCCGAGGCGGGCAGAUCACAAGGUCAGUAGAUCGAGACCAUCCUGACCAACAUGGUGAAACCCCCUCUCUACUAAAAAUACGAAAAUUAGGCCGGGCACAGUGGCUCAUGCCUGUAAUCCCAGAACUUUGGGAGGCUGAGGUGGGCGGAUCAUGAGGUCAGGAGAUCAAGACCAUCCUGGCUAACAUGGUGAAACCCCAUCUCUACUAAAAAUACAAAAAAUUAGCCGGACAUGUUGGCGGGCACCUGUAGUCCCAGCUACUCGGGAGGCUGAGGCAGGAGAAUGGCCUGAACCCGGGAGGCGGAGCUUGCAGUGAGCCAAGGCCACGCCACUGCACCCCAGCCUGGGUGACAGAGCGAGACUCCUCCUCAAUUUAAAAAAAAAUACAAAACUUAGCCAGGCGUGGUGGCCCACACCUGUAGUCCCAGCUACUUGGGAGGCUGAGGCAGGAGAAUGGCGUCAACCCGGGAGGCGGAGUUUGCGUGAGCCGAGAUCGCCCCACUGCACUCCAGCCUGGGUGACAGAGCGAGACUCUGUCUCAAAAAAAAAAAAAAAAAAAAAAAAAAGUUUGUAAUUUAAAAGUUUGAGCAUCACUGGGCUAGAUGGGGGUCCUGUAGAUAACCGGGACCCAAAUAGGCUUUAGGUACAGAGAUACAGGAGAACCAGAUUUGGGGUGCCGCUCUAGCCACUGUGUCCAGGAGGGAACCUUCCCAACCGCCCUAAAAGCUCUGAAAACUACAGUUAGAGAAGUGGCCACUAGGUGGCAAUAAUGUCAUUUCACAAAUUGGAUUUAAAACGCUUUUUUUUUUUUUUUUUUUUUUUGGUUUUUGGUUGUUUUUUUUUUUUCCCCGGAAACUUGUAUUCUAGCUGUGAACUGGCCCAGGUCCAUGGCCCUUAGGUGUAAUCUCCCCCUGGAAGGGCACAACAGGUGCAAAGUUUCCAUGAUGAGAAGGAGCCUGUGUUGUUUAAAGAAAUCACGGAGACUGGUGUGGCCUGAGCCCAGAGUGACAGGGAAGCUGGGUUUGCAGGGGGCCCGUGGAGGGCACUGGGAGUAACACGGUGUGUGGACCACGGGGAGUGGGACCAUGACAAGGUUUAAGGAGGAUAGGGGGUGGGGCUGUGCUUCAGAACGAACCUGCCAGUUAUCCAUGCCAUAGAUCUGGAGUCAGCAAACUUUUUCUGUCAAGGUCCAGGUCGUCAAUAUUGUCAGCUUUAGGGACCUUACCAUCUCCGUUGCAAUGACUGAACUCUGCUGCUGUCUGGCGAAAGCAGCCAUAGAUGAGACAUCAACGAAUGGGCUUGGCUGUGUUCCACUAAAACUUUGUUUAUAAACACAGAAGCUUCCAUUUCAUAUCAUAGUACAUGUCAUACCUUGUAGCCUUUGGGUUUGUUUUCAACCACUUUUAAAAUGUUAAAACUACUCUAGGCCAGGUGCAUUCACUCAUGCCUGUAAUCCCAGCACUUUGAGAGGCCAAGGGAGGAGGAUUGCUUGAAGCCAGGAGUUCGAGACUGGAGUGGGCAACAUAGUGAGACCUCCCCCAUCUCUACAAAAAUUUUUUAAUUAGCUGGGCAUGGUGGUGCAUGCCUGUAGUCUCAGCUACUCAGGAGGCUGAGGAAGGAGGAUCACUUAAGCCCAGGAGGUCAAGGCUGCAGUGAGCUAUGAUUGCACCACCGCACUCCAG